UGGCCACAGCUUUGUAAGAUAGAGGCAAAAGCCAAAAGUAAUGCACAUAUAAUAUUCUCUGCCUUGGGCGACAUCUGUGUUGUGUUGGCUGUAGUCAGAAAGAUAUGUGUCUUAAGGCACCAGAAACUUCCACCCAUUUUGGGAAAGGGAUAUUUUUCUCAAUAAAUAGUUAUAUGGCUUAUUUAUAAAGCCCCAAUCUUAAUGUUCUCAUUUAAUCUAAGGAGUGUAAAGGAAUUAAACUGUGCACAUUCCCAAAACACACACGGAAACAUAUACCAUGUCCUUCACAAGGAAACAGGGUAUUCUGGUAAGAUCUACAUUCCCACAUGCUUAAGACAGUCAUAAUUUCAAGUCAGUUGAACCAGUAUUUGUUCAGUGCCUCUAAUUUGCCCAGUGUUGAGCCACAUAGGCACUUGGGAGUUUGAAAGAUUCUAGGAUGUGGAUGAUGUCCUCAAGGUGCUUAUAAUUAGAAGGCAAAACUCCUCCCCUAGCAAACCUCACCUGGCAUUCUGCAGCAGAAACUGUAUGUGUUCUCUGGGGGAAAUCUUGUUGCAAAAAAUAUUUAUCGAUUUGCAUGAAAAGGUGCCAAUAGAGCUAAGAAAUAUUUUUAGCUGUAUUGUGUUUGACCCUUUGUGGACUUGUGACCCUUUGUGGACUUGUAGAAAUUUCAGUGUUUAUUCUUCAGGGUCAUUUAAGACAAAUGGUCAUGCUGUUUGGAGUGACAAAAAUGGCUUGUGGGACCCAAAGUAAUAAAGAACAGAUUGAUUCUAUUCUUUUAUAGAUUGGUAAUUCUUAGACUUUGCUGCACAAUUGUUCUCCUGGGGAGCUAUUAAUAUUACAAAUUCCAGUGCCUGGGUUGAGUCAAUCUCUGGAGGUGGGACUCAAGCCCCAGUUCUUUUUAAAACUUCCCAAGUAAUUCCUAAGUGCCACCAAGUUUGAGAUCUAGUGAUACAGAUGACUUUAUCAACAACCUUUUUUUUGUUGUUGUUUAUUUGUUUGUUUUAGCCUAAGCCUUCUAGGGUGAGUUUUGGAAUGGGCUUUUUAUAAUGAUGGGGGUGGGUGUUGACUAAAGAACUUUCAGCUUUCUGGAAGCUCACCCUCUGUUCUCUGUACUAGUGAACUCAGUGUAGAUGGAGGUAUGCUUUCUCCCUUUCCAACAAACCUGGUAAUAUGAUGCCAAGCCAGUCACUCAACCAUCUAUGUUACCUAAGGUUCCCUGAACCUUGAGUGUUUUUAUUACAGCAGCCCAAAUGUUCUGAAAAUCUUGAUUAUGUCUCUUAAGGGAAGGUAGUUUUAUAAUUAAUUACAUGUGUCCCUUGAAAUUAUUUUUACAUUGUCUGAAACCCCCAUGGAAGAGGAAGCCCAUUCUUGGUGUACUUGCAGCUAGUAGAAGUAGCUCAUUAAAAUACAGGGGUUACUCAAUUCCUGAUAACUCACUAUAGAUUUUUUUUUUUUCAGACAGGGUCUUGCUCACUCACCCAGGCUGGAGUGCAGUGUUGGUAUCAUAGCUCACUGUAACCUCAAAACCCAGGGCUCAAGUGAUCGUCCCACCUGAGCCUCCCAAGUAGCUGAGAUUACAGUUGUGCGCCACCAUGCCUGGCCAAUCUAAAAAAUUUUUUUAGAGACAGAAUCUCUCUAUGUUGCCCAGGCUGUUCUCGAAUUCCUGGCCUCAAGUGAUCCUUCUGCUGUGGCCUCCCAAAGUGUUAGGAUUACAGGUGUGAGGCCACUACCCCCAGCCACCUCACUAUACAUUCUUAGGGUUGGAAAGUAUUUUCAAAAUACUCUAGUACAGCGGUUCUCAAGGUGCAGCAUCAGCCUCACCUGGACUUGUUAGAAAUGUACAUGUUCACGCUCCACCCCCAGAUCUUCCGAGUCAGACACAGAGAUGAGGGUGUAGGUGGUGGUGAGGGGUGGGCCCAGCAUCUGUGUUUUAGGAAGUUCUCCUCUCCGGGUGCCCACCAAAAUUUGAAUUACUGCUGUUAUUUCACCUUGUCAGAAACUGAGGUACCCCAGUCCUCAGAUCUGUCUCUGCACCAUGGCCAGAUCAUCCUAACUUUUCUGUGUCAUGAAUAACUGCCUUAAGAAAACACCCACCAUCCUAAAAUCAUAAGGCAUAAAGAAACCUUAAAUGUUGUCUCAUCUGACCCUCCCAUUUCACAGAUGAGAAAACUAAGGUCGAUAGGGUGACAUGAAGUCAAUAAGAUGUAGAGUUAUUGGUGACAGAGCUUUUGGUCUACUUAAAACCGACACAGUCUUCCUCCCCCACUGGCCCACAUUGCCUCUCCAGUUUUAUGUGGACUUCUAGUAUUUGGCUGAAAUCACGUCAGUUAAAAUGUCUAGGUUAAUUGUCAGGCAACUCUAGAAAAAGACCAACAGAAUUUUAAUUCUUUAAAAUUAAUCCAAAAUUCUUUCAUUUCAAAUUGGCUUGAAUUUUAUAACUGUCUUUGUACAUUUAAUAGAAAAAAAUAUCGGUGAUGUAAACUGCUGAAAAGAAAAUUCACAGAACAUGGGGACCAGUCCUGGAACAUAGGUUUCAUCCCAACAUCGUGUAGAUUAGGCACUUAACAGCGCCUCAGAGGCACACACUGAAAUUGCAUUUUCUUCCGAUUUGGUUAAAAGGAAAAACGUGACAAGAAGUCUGUUUGUUGAAUACUUUACAAUUUUAUACUUGAUGUGGUUAGUGAUAUUUACAUAAUUUUGUCCGUGUUCAAAGACUGAAUCUAAUCCACAUUCUCUGUAGAGCUUCAUCUUUCAAAGCAUUGUAGCAAUACACAGGGAACAUUAAGCCAAGAAAACGAAGGGAGAACACACAGCUAUUAUCUACAUACACAUAUACAUGGAGCAGGCAUGUCCAUGGAUAAAUUUUUUUUUGGUUUUUUUUGUGGGUUUUUUUGAGACAGAGUCUGGCUCUGUUGCCCAGGCUGGAGUGCAGUGGUGUGAUCUCAGCGAUUCUCCUGCCUCAGCCUCCCGAGUAGGUGGGACUACAGGCGCGCACCACUAUGCCUGGCUAAUUUUUGUAUUUUUUUUAGUAGAGACCAGGUUUCGCCAUGUUGGUCAGGCUGGUCUAGAACUCCUGACCUUAAGUGAUCCGCCUGCCUCACCCUCCGAAAGUGCUGGGAUUACAGGCGUUAAGCCACCAUGCCUAGCCCAUUGAAUAGAAGUGUUUAUUGGUUCCACACACCUACCAUGUGCUAGGUAUUGUGAUGUGGUGUGGGACACAUAUAGUUCCUAUCUUCGAAUGAUCAUGGGACAGUGGGAAAGUCAGACAAGUGCUUCAGUAGACAAUUAUGAGAGCAGGUGGUGGAGUUAGAAGAGAGUACAGUUGAGGCUGAUGGAGCAGAAGGGCAUUCUGAAGAUCAUGAAAGGGACAUCAGUGCACACUGGAUGGGAGCAGAAACCAGAGAAGGCUGCCUGGAGGAGGUGUCCUGUGAGCUACAUUUCAAAGUAUGGUAGAUAUCUAGGUGAAGGGGAGUAGGGAGGAGGUUGUGUAGGGAGAGGGGCCAGUAUAUGCCAAGGCAUCAAUGCUUGUGUGUACAUUUUCUAUCACUGGGCCAGGAUUGAUCUAUAAAUCCCUAUGUAUUUCUUUGUGUGUAUAAACAUUAGCAAUUUGGUUUCUUAGAGAAACCAAAUGCUUUGCAUAGCAGUUUUAAAAUAUACAUUUCGAAAAGCUCAUUUUUCCAUUACAAAAGACUCAGAUGUUCCCAAGAAAAGUUUCUCAGUUGAGAGGUCACCAGAUCUUAUGUUACCGAGAAAAUGGAAAGAUUUCCCCUAACCCCAGAAGUCAAACCAGCUUCCUCAAUUUGAGACUGCACAAAACCAAUUAAUUUUUGCCCAUUGUGGAUUUUCUUAAUAAUUGCAUCUCCGACAAACCAACUCCUGUCCUAAAUGGAUUUGAGCCACAUUUCACUCUGAAAGCUGUGGGUCCAUCUGGGAAAUGUCUUUGUAGAUGAGAGAAUUUUAUAAUAAAGUAUUUUUGGUAUUUCAUUUACUAAAUCUUCAGGGAUAUAGGUAAGAGAGCCUCCGUGCUGAACUGACUGCCUAACAGAACAAGGUUAGAGAGAAUGAAAUUAUUUCAUGCUGUCUGGCCUGCAACACAUGCCUCUGAACGAAGCCAUAUACAGUCGCGGGUCGCAUAAUGAUGUUCUGGUCAAUAACAGAUGGCAUAUACAAUGGUGGUCCCAUAAGAUUAUAAUACUGCAUUUUUACUGUACUUGUCUAGGUUUAAACAUAUUUAGAUAUGCACAAAUACUCACCAUUGUGUUCCAGUUGCCUCCAGCAUUCAGUACAGGAACAUGCUGUGCAAGUUUGUAGCCUAGGAGCAAUAGGGUAUAUCAUAUAGCCUAGGUGUGUAUGUACACUCUAUGAUGUUCGCAUGACAAAAUUGCCUAACAACACAUUUCUCAAGACAUGUCUCUAUUGUUAAGCAGCACAUGACUGUAUAUAUAACAAUGGUUUCUUUAAAAGCACUCCCAGGAGUGGCCAGGUGCAGAAAUAGCUGAAUUUGUGAGCAAUGAUAAUGAUAGUUAAUAUAAUUAUCAUAUUUUCCAGAGCACCUGCACAUCACGUUUGAUCUUUACAGUGAGUGGAACAGACAUUACGAUCUCCAUUUGACAGAUGAGGAAAUUAAACCUUAGAGUUAUCAGAUUUCAAAGGUGAAGGGACCUUAGAGAUCCUUUCAUCCAGCUUUCUCAUUUUACAAAAAAAAGAACUCCCUGAGAUCCAGGGAAACUAACUGACCUAGGAUCCCACAGGGAGUGAAUAAGGGCUGUUGGGCCAGGCCCAGGUCUUCUGAUUUCUAGCUUCCUGAUUUUGCACUCCAUUGCGCUAUUCUCAGUCUUCAGUGUGUUAGAGGAAACUUGGUAGGUUAUGCAUUUGUUCUUAAGGAGAAAUUUUGUUGAUAUCAGUCCUAGGCACUAUUUUAUAAAUGCACACAUGUGGAAAAAUCCCUUAUUUUCCUGCUUUUUUUCUAUAUAUAGAUACAGGCAGAUACACAGACAGAUAGACACACCACAUGUGGAUGUCACUGGGGAGAUGAAGGUGGGAUUGAACUUAGCAGAGUCUCAAAGGGGGCUUCAGCUUUAUCUGUCAAAUAUUCUUUUAUUAAAAAAUUUUGAAGCAAAAUGACCAUUACAGUAGCAUUUAUUCAUUUUGGAUAAUGGGCACUGAAUUCAUAAGUGUUUGUUUUCCUCUUCAUAUUUCUGUAUUUUAAAAUUUUCAAAAAAAACCAAAUAUGGAUAUUAAAAAUAAAUUCUCACCUAUAAUACCAUACCCUCAUUUUAUAAAAAUAAAGAAUAUUUUCAAAGAAAUAAAAAUGGUUCAGAAGGAUGGAAAGAAAACUAUACUAUGGGACUCGUUAGUUAAGUUGACAUUAAUCCUCUGCUUUAAGUCUUUCCUGUGAUGACACUAGCAGAAUGUGUAUCAUUUUCUCUGCAUUUGCUGCAGGAUCAGUUCUCUUUGGCAGGUUUUGAGCCGUUCUAAUAAGUCCAGCAUGAAAGGCAGGCCUCUCGUGUCAGUUCUAAACCCACCAGCUGCCCCAUUGUGACUGCAUAGUCCCCUGGUUCUGAGACUGUGCUCUGCCUGAUAAGCGACGUACGGAGCACAGUGGACUGAAAGCCCGGGGAUCUGAUACCAAACAUGUUAGUUAAACUCAUGUUUAACUAACCCAAACUCAUGUUUAACUGGCCCAAAGGAAGUAGGCCCAGAAAUGUGGUUUUUGGAGCUCCCUUUAAUGAACGUGUAAACAGAGGAUAGAAUAUUGGCCUUACAGUUUAAAAACCCUCCUUCAAGUCCCAGUCAAGUCCCUUAUUCACUGGAUGACCUCACACGGUUCAUCUGAUCUUUCUUGGUCUCAGUCUUCUUACUAUAGACUGGAAAUGGUCAUAUUUGACUUAGCUGUCCAUAUGGCUGUUCUGGAGAUGAGACAGCUAAUGAAGUGAGAACACUCAUUAACACACCAACUGAAAAACACAAAACAAAAGAGAGAUGAUAGGAUUAUAUUGCUGUUAUGAAUCAUUCCAAGAGGUGUCAUGGUGAUAUGAAUCAUCAUAUGGUAAUGUCAUGGCUAAGGCCCAAACACAGAAUAGCAGCAUUGACCCAGUAGUCUCGAAAUUAGUCACAGAGGCCAAGCUAGUGAAGACCCAGCAGCCCUAUUGUUAUCAAGAAAGAGCACUAUCCAAAAGGUGUGUGGCCUCAUCUUCUCCUUGCAAAGAGAGAAUUCAUCUGGUAUAUGUUGAUAGGCGUGUAUCCGACCACAGCUACCUCCAUCAGCCCUGAGGACAGAGGCAGCCUGCAUUCCAGUCCCAGCUCUUCUCUGUCUCGGUGUGUGACUUAGGCGGUUUCACAGAGGACGCCAACUUCAUUGGCUUUUGCGGUUUUUUGUUUGUUUGUUUUUUGUUGUUUUCUUUUUGUUUGUUUUGUUUUGUUUUUGUCUGUAGAAUGAGUGAGUUAAACUAAAUUGUCUGUAAGGCCUCAGCUCACUCUUAAAGUGUGAUCACUAGCUAGAGUUUGAACUUUAGCCCCAAUAUGACUGUUGUGUUGUCAUUGUCACCUUUGUAACCUGACAUUCAGGAAUGUCCCUCUCUAGUUCAUAUUCUGACCUAGCUUCUGAAAGCAUUAUAGCAGAGUUGAGAAUUUUUGAUCUAGGAAAGAUAAAUAUUAAAAAGAAAUUCCCACCAAAAUACCAUAAAUAAGGAAUGUUUUAAAGAAAAAUGGUUCAGAAGGAAGGAAAACUAUAAUGUAGUUCUUGUUAGUUAAGUUGACAUUAAUCCUCUCUUUGCUUUAAGUCUCUCCUGUGUUGACACUAGCAGAAUGUGUCAUAAAGACAUGGAAAGAUCAUAAAUUCUCAACUCUGCUCUAAAGAUCUGACCUUCAGCGUUGCAUUUAUUUGGCCACACCUUUAUAGUGUGGUCAUACCUAGAAAAUAUUUUCUUGCCUGGUCAUCAGCCCUCUCACCUCGAUUACUUUCUAUAUUUUAGCACAAAAGAAGAAAUGGCGCAUUCACCACUCAGCCAGUUGCACUGGAAGUGAAUUUAAAUUCCUGAACUGGUUAUCUUGGAAGAUAUUGUGCUUAUUGCAGAUGUGGCCGGUGCAUGAGUUUAGGCACUACCAUGCUCUGGGCUGUGGUUCUUGGCUCCUGCUUCUGGAUGGCUGGACAUUACCAGGAGAGAGCCUGCUGAUACAUCUACGCACAUUCACUCUACUGCACUUCAGCUGUGUCCUUGUUAUUCCACAGCCCUUUAAGUCCUGGUUCACCAACCAGAUGUUAAGACUCUCUUGGAUCCCUCAAAUCCCAUCCCCAUGCCUGCUGCCUCCUCUCUCAGCAGUUGCCCACUCCUUAUCUUCUAAUCCUCUUUUCUCCCUAUGAUGAUGAUAGUGACCCUGUAGCUCCAACUACUGGGUCCUCACAGUCAGUCCACUCCUGCAGAGGAAACUGGAGGGUGACCAGGAACCUUCAAGUCAAUGUGGGCCACAGACAGGAACCGUCUUUAAAAGAUGGUUAAAUGCCCGUGGUUUACGUAGGUUGGCUUUCUUUAAGCAAAUAAAGGAAAUGCAUUGCUUCAUGUCCAGCAAAGUACAGGGUGGAUUCAGGAGAAGCUGGCUCAAGGCAUUCCUAGGAAGUCAUCAAGGAGCUGCCUGUACCUCUGUCUUCAGGCCAGCAUCUUCUGAGUUGGCUUUAUUCUCAAGCAGGCUGUCAUUAAGUGAUGGCUUAACAACAAUUUAGCAACCAUGGCAUGACAGAGAAUCAUGCCUGAUAGCUCUAACAAAGUAUCCGAGAGUGUUCCCCCAUGAGCCAAUCACUGUUGCCAGAGGGAUGUGGUUCUUGGACUGGCCAGGUCUGAGACACGUUGCUUGGGCCCCUAUUUGUGCAGAAUUGGCCCCUGACUACAUUCCCAGAGGGUCUUUGGAUGUUUGGUCAGAUGGUCUGUACUCUGGGGGGAUCAAUUCAUACCAGCAAGGUCCAGUCAGCCCCUACACCUACCACCGCCUCUCUAGUGGAAGCCACUUUUGCAUCUAAUUGUCUUGGGAAUUGUGUUGGUUUUCUAUUGCUGCUGUAACAAAUUGCCACAAAUUUAAUGGCUUAUAAUAACAUACAUGUAUUAUCUUACAGUUCUGGAGGCCAUAAGUCCAAAACCAGCCUCACUGGACUACGGUCAAGGUGUUAGUUCCUUCUGGAGGCUCUAAGGGACAAUCUGUUUCCUGGUCUUUUCUAGUUUCUAAGAGGCUUCCUGCAUUUCUUUGGCUCAUGGCCCCUUCCUCCAUCUUCAAAGCCAGCAGCAAAGCAUCUUCUCUCCUCUCUGACUUCUGUUUCCAUCCUUAUAUCUUCUCGCUGACUCUGAUCCUCCUGCUUCCGUCUUAGAAGGACUCUUGUGAUUACAUUGGGCAUACCAAAUUAAAUUCAGAAAUUCAGAUAAUCAAGAUCUUUAAUUCAAUCAUGUCUGCAAAGUCCCCUUUACCAUGUAAGAUAACAUAUUCACAGCCUCUGUGGGUUAGAAUGUGAACAUUUUUAUUAUUCAGCCUACUGCAGGGAUUAUCCACUCAAUUUAAAAACCUGAACUUAGACAGAGAAAGAGUGUACUGAAGCUCCUGCAUUGGAGUGGGAAAUUGUAGAUAGUGACCUAGGAAGGUGACUUUGUACCUGCUUGUAGGUUUAGUUUUAUUUGCUUCUUGGGUGUAUUUAGAUUGUCCUUUUUGAGCUGUUUGUGGGUUUUUCUCCACAGAAUUGGGUACUCAUAAAAGAGGUGUCCAUAUUGCCUCAAAGCCACCAGAUUCUGAUGAGCCAUACCCCUUAUCUUCCUUCUUCAUUUUGUUCACGGCAAUUACUUUGUGCCCAUAAAGUGGGAGGCAGUGUGCUGAGGAAAUACAAGAUUCUCCAAGACACACUCCUUUCUCUUGUGGAACUUAUGUCUGGUGGAGUAGAAAGGCACGCACGCAAUUAUUUUUAACCCAAGGCACAGGAUGUGCUGAGUGAUAUAAAAGUGACAAACUAAGGAGUGGGAAGACAGCAGGAGACAUCAGUUCCAGCUUCCAGGGGUGUCAGAUCAUGCACCCCAAUUUUUGGUUCAGAAAUAUGAUCACUACUAUAUGCACCUCAAUUUCAGGUUAUUAACUAUUGCAGGCUAAGAAUUUUAGGGCUUUAAAAAUAGUAUGAUGUGUUUUUUCUUCUUUGUCUAGGGUGUUUGGAUGAAAGCAGGUGCUCAGCUCUGAUGAUUCAUGUGAAAUCACUUCUACUCAAGGUUGACUAAAGUUGGGAAUGAUGAAAAUUUCCUAGUCAAAGCAAAAAUUAAGAAGAAAACCUGUGCCGCCAAGCUCCUGGACAAGAACCCAUUCUCGGUCAGUAACCCGAACCCUCUGCUUCCUUCACCUGCCAGUCUCCAGCUGGCUCAACUGCAGGCCCAGCUCACCCUCCACCGGCUGAAGCUGGCACAGACAGCUGUCACCAACAACACUGCAGCCGCCACAGUCCUGAACCAAGUCCUCUCCAAAGUGGCCAUGUCCCAGCCUCUCUUCAAUCAACUGAGGCAUCCGUCUGUGAUCACUGGCCCCCACGGCCAUGCUGGGGUUCCCCAACAUGCUGCAGCCAUACCCAGUACCCGGUUUCCCUCUAAUGCAAUUGCCUUUUCACCCCCCAGCCAGACACGAGGCCCCGGACCCUCCAUGAACCUUCCCAACCAGCCACCCAGUGCCAUGGUGAUGCAUCCUUUCACUGGGGUAAUGCCUCAGACCCCUGGCCAGCCAGCAGUCAUCUUGGGCAUUGGCAAGACUGGGCCUGCUCCAGCUACAGCAGGAUUCUAUGAGUAUGGCAAAGCCAGCUCUGGCCAGACAUAUGGCCCUGAAACAGAUGGUCAGCCUGGCUUCCUGCCAUCCUCGGCCUCAACCUCGGGCAGUGUGACCUAUGAAGGGCACUACAGCCACACAGGGCAGGAUGGUCAAGCUGCCUUUUCCAAAGAUUUUUACGGACCCAACUCCCAAGGUUCACAUGUGGCCAGCGGAUUUCCAGCUGAGCAGGCUGGGGGCCUGAAAAGUGAGGUCGGGCCACUGCUGCAGGGCACAAACAGCCAAUGGGAGAGCCCCCAUGGAUUCUCGGGCCAAAGCAAGCCUGAUCUCACAGCAGGUCCCAUGUGGCCUCCACCCCACAACCAGCCCUAUGAGCUGUACGACCCCGAGGAACCAACCUCAGACAGGACACCUCCUUCCUUCGGGGGUCGGCUUAACAACAGCAAACAGGGUUUUAUCGGUGCUGGGCGGAGGGCCAAGGAGGACCAGGCGUUGCUAUCUGUGCGGCCCCUGCAGGCUCAUGAGCUGAACGACUUUCACGGUGUGGCCCCCCUCCACUUGCCGCAUAUCUGUAGCAUCUGUGACAAGAAGGUGUUUGAUUUGAAGGACUGGGAGCUGCAUGUGAAAGGGAAGCUGCACGCUCAGAAAUGCCUGGUCUUCUCUGAAAAUGCUGGCAUCCGGUGUAUACUUGGUUCGGCAGAGGGAACAUUGUGUGCUUCUCCCAACAGCACAGCUGUUUAUAACCCUGCUGGGAAUGAAGAUUAUGCCUCAAAUCUUGGAACAUCAUACGUGCCCAUUCCAGCAAGGUCAUUCACUCAGUCAAGCCCCACAUUUCCUUUGGCUUCUGUGGGGACAACUUUUGCACAGCGGAAAGGGGCUGGCCGUGUGGUGCACAUCUGCAAUCUCCCUGAAGGAAGCUGCACUGAGAAUGACGUCAUUAACCUGGGGCUGCCCUUUGGAAAGGUCACUAAUUACAUCCUCAUGAAGUCGACUAAUCAGGCCUUUUUAGAGAUGGCUUACACAGAAGCUGCACAGGCCAUGGUCCAGUAUUAUCAAGAAAAAUCUGCUGUGAUCAAUGGUGAGAAGUUGCUCAUUCGGAUGUCCAAGAGAUACAAGGAAUUGCAGCUCAAGAAACCCGGGAAGGCCGUGGCUGCCAUCAUCCAGGACAUCCAUUCCCAGAGGGAGAGGGACAUGUUCCGGGAAGCAGACAGAUAUGGCCCAGAAAGGCCGCGGUCUCGUAGUCCGGUGAGCCGGUCACUCUCCCCGAGGUCCCACACUCCCAGCUUCACCUCCUGCAGCUCUUCCCACAGCCCUCCGGGCCCCUCCCGGGCUGACUGGGGCAAUGGCCGGGACUCCUGGGAGCACUCUCCCUAUGCCAGGAGGGAGGAAGAGCGAGACCCGGCUCCCUGGAGGGACAACGGAGAUGACAAGAGGGACAGGAUGGACCCCUGGGCACAUGAUCGCAAACACCACCCCCGGCAACUGGACAAGGCUGAGUUGGACGAGCGACCAGAAGGAGGGAGGCCCCACCGGGAGAAGUACCCGAGAUCUGGGUCUCCCAACCUGCCCCACUCUGUGUCCAGCUACAAAAGCCGUGAAGACGGCUACUACCGGAAAGAGCCCAAAGCCAAGUCGGACAAGUAUCUGAAGCAGCAGCAGGAUGCCCCCGGGAGGUCCAGGAGGAAAGACGAGGCCAGGCUGCGGGAAAGCAGACACCCCCAUCCGGAUGACUCAGGCAAGGAAGAUGGGCUGGGGCCAAAGGUCACUAGGGCCCCUGAGGGCGCCAAGGCCAAGCAGAAUGAGAAAAAUAAAACCAAGAGAACUGAUAGAGACCAAGAAGGAGCUGAUGAUAGAAAAGAAAACACAAUGGCAGAGAAUGAGGCUGGAAAAGAGGAACAGGAGGGCAUGGAAGAAAGCCCUCAAUCAGUGGGCAGACAGGAGAAAGAAGCAGAGUUCUCUGAUCCGGAAAACACAAGGACAAAGAAGGAACAAGAUUGGGAGAGUGAAAGUGAGGCAGAGGGGGAGAGCUGGUAUCCCACUAACAUGGAGGAGCUGGUGACAGUGGACGAGGUUGGGGAAGAAGAAGAUUUUAUCGUGGAACCAGACAUCCCAGAGCUGGAAGAAAUUGUGCCCAUUGACCAGAAAGACAAAAUUUGCCCAGAAACAUGUCUGUGUGUGACAACCACCUUAGACUUAGACCUGGCCCAGGAUUUCCCCAAGGAAGGAGUCAAGGCCGUAGGGAAUGGGGCUGCAGAAAUCAGCCUCAAGUCACCCAGAGAACUGCCCUCUGCUUCCACAAGCUGUCCCAGUGACAUGGACGUGGAAAUGCCUGGCCUAAAUCUGGAUGCUGAGCGGAAGCCAGCUGAAAGUGAGACAGGCCUCUCCCUGGAGGAUUCAGAUUGCUACGAGAAGGAGGCAAAGGGAGUGGAGAGCUCAGAUGUUCAUCCAGCCCCUACAGUCCAGCAAAUGUCUUCCCCUAAGCCAGCAGAGGAGAGGGCCCGGCAGCCAAGCCCAUUUGUGGAUGAUUGCAAGACCAGGGGGACCCCCGAAGAUGGGGCUUGUGAAGGCAGCCCCCUGGAGGAGAAAGCCAGCCCCCCCAUCGAAACUGACCUCCAAAACCAAGCUUGCCAAGAAGUGUUGACCCCGGAAAACUCCAGGUACGUGGAAAUGAAAUCUCUGGAGGUGAGGUCACCAGAGUACACUGAAGUGGAACUGAAACAGCCCCUUUCUUUGCCCUCUUGGGAACCAGAGGAUGUGUUCAGUGAACUUAGCAUUCCUCUAGGGGUGGAGUUCGUGGUUCCCAGGACUGGCUUUUAUUGCAAGCUGUGUGGGCUGUUCUACACGAGCGAGGAGACAGCAAAGAUGAGCCACUGCCGCAGCGCUGUCCACUACAGGAACUUACAGAAAUAUUUGUCCCAGCUGGCCGAGGAGGGCCUCAAGGAGACCGAGGGGGCAGAUAGCCCGAGGCCAGAGGACAGCGGAAUCGUGCCACGCUUCGAAAGGAAAAAGCUCUGAUGCUUCUGCUUCUGCUGCUACUGCUGCUGCUGCAAGGUUGGAAAGGAGAGCUUGCUGAAGUGGGGCCUUCCUGAUUCUGGGGACAGGACUAAAGCCUGAGAGGAAGGAAAACCAAGCAGGGCACAUUGCUUGGGCUUGUUCCCAGAGACUCAGUGAAAUGCCCCUGAUAUGUCUCCAGGAGCAAGUCACCCAGGUGUGUCCAGCCCACUGAGGGUCACCAACUCUCUCCCUGCUGACUCUUGUUUCUCUCAAUCUUUCAAUUCGUUUUUCUCUCUUUUCCUCUUGUUCUUUCUCUCCCUCCCUCCUUAUGUGCCAAGGAUCGUUUCCUUUUCACAAAACCCAACUUCUCAGGGAUUUUCACAGUGUUUAAAUUCUUGGUAGGAUAUAACAGGUCAGGCCUAGCUGAGUCAGGCAAGGAAAAGGUUUAAUGGAAACUCCUGGGUCAGGCGAACCCCUGCAGUGAGUCUACAGCAGUAUCUCUGCCUGGUGUCCCAUGUAUCCCCUGCAUGAGGAGCUGAGUCAGGUCUGCAGUCCUGGUGAGGGGACAUCACGGACAAUCUGUUGGCAGAGCUGGGAGGGUCUUCAUUAACCUCUUCCUCCAACUGGGCCACCCUUUUGAAAAGCCCCUGUUUUUAAUAACUGUUUCAUCCUCUCAGUUAUUCUAGAAAUCUGCCAGACUUAUGCCUUAAAGUAAAAUUAAAUGAAUUUUAGAGAAGAUGAAAAGAGCCCUUCAUUUUGGAAGCUCUGAUAAGUUUCCUCCAAACUUAUUCCCCUCCUCUUGAUUUCAGGAGAUGUCAGGGUUUUUCUAUUCUGGACAAUGAAUUUGGUACAGAGUCACUGUAAUUAAAUAUAAAAACAGAAGCAUCUUCCUCCAGCUAAAGCAGCAGUUGGCGCGGGCUUAGGUUGAAUGCUGGCCUCUCUGCAAAGCACAGCUUUGGCUCGAGAGGCACAGCUCCAGGCUGUGGAAAACAGAGUUGUCUUGGGGGUUAAAUGAGCUUAUUUAAGUCAAGGAAACAUCAUCUGUCCUUGAUUCAGCCUUGGUGCCUGCACUCUGGGGUACAACCACCUCACAGUAGGAUGGUUUUUAAAUGGCCCCCCAGUUGGGGGAGAAGCUAAGGAAAGAGAAGGCUGCAGAUCCAAAGAGUGGCAUUGAAGUUUGCUGGGUGUCUGUAGGUGGACCCUUUCCAGCUGGGCAGAUAGUUGAGGGCUCCCUGGGUUUGACUGUAUGUGCAGACUUUGAUACCAAAAUGUUAUGAAAAGUCGUGAUUCCCGCUGCUCUUUCUGGUACUGGAGGGUGGGUACCUUCAGGCUGUGGGGUCUCUAGCCUGAUAUUCCAUUGAAAGGGUGUGGGAUAAAGGUGCUGGGGGAAAUGAGGCUCUGCCACAGCCAUAGAGAGGCCCUCGGGCAGUUAAGAAGGGAGCCUGGAGCUGUUUUCAUGAGCAGAGAUACUCUCCUGAAAGCACCCUUCAUAGCUUAGCCCAGGAAAAAUAAAACAAGGAAGACAGGUCACUCUCCCCUAGGCAGUUCCUGUUGUUUCUGUUCCUGACCUUGGGCAGGCAGACUGAGAAGGGACUGUGUAGGGUUUUGUUUUGUUUUUUUUCAUUUUCCUUUUUAUGGCAUGUGAGAGCAUACUGUACAUUCUGUCCUCUGUACUAAUGGAGGAAGGGCAGAGAGAUUAGUUCAAGGCUAACAUUUUAUAUCAGGUAACUGAGGCACACAAAGGGAACAAAUGAAGAACAUAAAAUGAUCAGUGUAAACCUGAAAGCACGCAGUCAUUGGCAAGGGACAGGCUCAUGGGAGCUGGUGAGAGAGAGCAGUUAAGGCAAGCACCAGGGGAAAGCAGACCAACUUGAACAGAUGUGAUGCGGAGAGGUUGGAAGAAGCAAGAAACCUGAACUCAUCAUCAGGCUAUUAAAUAAAAUUUAUAGGAGGCUGUUGGUUUGGACUGAGCUCCUGCAAUAGGCCCAACAGACCAAAACAAAAGGGAGUCACUCAUGUUGAAGUUCUGUCUUCCAGGAAAUCAGGAGAGAGAGAGAGAGAAAGAAUAGCCAAAUCCCCAAACAGGCCAGUUUUAACCAGCAUGAUGAAGUGUCCUUGGUUUUAACCUUUAUAAGGAAAGCAGCUUUGAGAUGACCAGUCUGGUUUUUGUUCUUUGUGUCUGCUUUCCUCAGCCCUUUUCUGUCUAUAAAGCCAACCUCCUCCGCUCAGCUCAUGGGAACACUCAUUCUAUUUUAUAGAAUGACAUGUUGCCCAAUUCUAGAAUCAAAAAUAAAGGCCAACUAAGAUCUUCAAAGUAAAUUUGUUGUAAUUUUAUCUUUUGAGAAGACCAUAUGGGGGCUGCUGAAAAGUUGGUAUCUCAAAUAAAGUCUGAAGAUCACGGCUCAGCCCAGAUUGUUCCCCUGGCCAACUCCACAGGUUUGAACCUGGCAUUCUGGACACCAGCUAUGCCUCCUCCAUUUCUCAGAAAACCUUUGAUCUUGUGUGUCUUUCUUCCUACUGAAGGGAAUUGUGGGGGCAGUUCUUUGGCCUUCUUGCUGAACUUUGCUGGAAAUAGCCCACAAUUUUUAUCAGAGGUUAGAACUGUACAUUAUCAGAGAGACUGGACACUUUAUCCCCUAGCAAAGUGGGAGAAGAUUUUACCAGCUCAUUCCACUCCACCCUGGCCUUCCCCCACCCCCCAUCCCCAGCAGCAUUUCCAUGGAAAUCCAGAUGGUCGUGUAGUGUUAUGGCUCUCUUGUGAUAGACUGGCCUUCAUAUUGGAGAGCUAGGGAGAGCCCCUGGGAGGGAGAGAGAUAAGGCGCUAUCUGCCUUCAAUCAGAACCUUCGGUUUAAAAUCAUCUAAGAGUCUAUACUUGUGUGUACAUACGUAUUUAUUUUUAUUUAUUUUUAUACAAUUCCAUUGGCAUGGUCCUUCACCGACCCUAUGAUUUGCACUUUUUAUUUCUAUGUGUGCCACACACAAUGCAGUAUUAAUGGCAACCAGGUAAAUAUUGAUUUAUUUUUUAAAGCUUUUCUUCAGUGUUUUGUCAACCAUUUCAAAGUGUCUCCCAAAAAAGGAUGCUGAAGAGCAAUUGCUCCCUUAAGCAACAGAUUCAUAUUUACCCUGGGUUAAUACAACAAAAGGCCUGUAUAAUUGUCUUUUCAUUGUUAACACCCAAAAUAGCAUCUAUCUAGACAGUAUCCCCAAAGAAUUUGGAAAAUCUGAUGGUGUGAGCAGCAGCCGUUAGUAUCAGGGUUUCCCAUUCUUGGACAGUCCGAGGCUGUGACCUGUUAGAUAAUUAGAUUAUACUUGAACUGGACCAGAGUUUGUUUUUUGAAUUUAUGAGAAAAACCAAAACACUAAGUUAAGUUUGAACUUGUAAAGUAUUGAAAUUUGUUGAGUGUCCUAUAAAUUGUCACUACUUUUCCUGAUCUGUAUAACUGACUGCAAAGUGUUUGUUUUUACAAAAGAGAAAAGAAAAGAUUUUUAAUAAAGAGAAUUUGAAAGCUG